GGCCACAUUCCUGCAGCAUGAUGGUUGGCAGUUAGCUUCCUGGAGUGUGGACGGGUCCUUCCCUGCCUGACUGACUUGUCCACAGGGCAGCAAGAAGAUGCGCCCCUUGGUGUGUCCCGAGUGUCUCCUGUAGGCAGCUGAGCUUUCGCAGGUCUGGCUGGGAGCCAAGGUUACCAAUCUGGGGGGUAACCCAGCCAUCAUCUGGAUGAGCGUUGGGGUCUUUCUGCUCUGGAUUGCAGGGCAGACGUCGUUUUGUGCUGGUCAGGCCCCUCGCCUGCCUGAUUCCCUUGGAGCCCCCCAAGACAGGAGAUGGGCAGAUGUCCUCUGAAGUGGCAUGGGCUGCUUGCUCACUGGCCUUCCCAGGACCCUGCCCAGGUGGUGCUGCUUGGCCCCAGGUCGAAUUCCUGUGCUGGCAGCAAGCAGGGGCCUGGGCCGUCGGCUGGCUGGGGCUCAUGCAGCCAUCCCCUUUGCAGCCAUCCGGGUGACCUGCAUAGGUUCCUGCGGGGUCUCCAACAAGGCUAAUGACACAGCGUGGGUAGUGGAGGAGGGUUACUUCAACAGUUCCCUGUCGCUGGCAGACAAGGGGAGCCUGCCCGCUGGAGAGCACAGCUUCCCCUUCCAGUUCCUGCUUCCUGCCACUGCACCCACGUCCUUUGAGGGUCCUUUCGGGAAGAUCGUGCACCAGGUGAGGGCCGCCAUCCACACGCCACGGUUUUCCAAGGAUCACAAGUGCAGCCUCGUGUUCUAUAUCUUGAGCCCCUUGAACCUGAACAGCAUCCCAGACAUUGAGGGAUCCAGCCUGCGCACACCUGCUAAGCCCCUCCCUGGCCCUCCCCCCAAGCAACCCAACGUGGCCUCUGCCACCAAGAAGUUCUCCUACAAGCUGGUGAAGACGGGCAGCGUGGUCCUCACAGCCAGCACUGAUCUCCGCGGCUAUGUGGUGGGGCAGGCACUGCAGCUGCAUGCCGACGUUGAGAACCAGUCAGGCAAGGACACCAGCCCUGUGGUGGCCAGUCUGCUGCAGAAAGUGUCCUAUAAGGCCAAGCGCUGGAUCCACGACGUACGGACCAUUGCGGAGGUGGAGGGUGCGGGCGUCAAGGCCUGGCGGCGGGCGCAGUGGCACGAGCAGAUCCUGGUGCCUGCCUUGCCCCAGUCGGCCCUGCCGGGCUGCAGCCUCAUCCACAUCGACUACUACUUACAGGUCUCUCUGAAGGCGCCGGAAGCUACUGUGACCCUCCCGGUCUUCAUUGGCAAUAUUGCUGUGAACCAUGCCCCAGUGAGCCCCCGGCCAGGCCUGGGGCUGCCUCCUGGGGCCCCACCCCUGGUGGUGCCUUCCGCACCACCCCAGGAGGAGGCUGAGGCUGAGGCUGCGGCUGGCGGCCCCCACUUCUUGGACCCCGUCUUCCUCUCCACCAAGAGCCAUUCGCAGCGGCAGCCCCUGCUGGCCACCUUGAGUUCUGUGCCUGGUGCGCCGGAGCCCUGCCCUCAGGAUGGCAGCCCUGCCUCACACCCGCUGCACCCUCCCUUGUGCAUUUCAACAGGUGCCACUGUCCCCUACUUUGCAGAGGGCUCCGGGGGGCCAGUGCCCACUACCAGCACCUUGAUUCUUCCUCCAGAGUACAGUUCUUGGGGCUACCCCUAUGGUGAGUCGACAGCCAGGGCUUGGCAGGGAGGGGACGCCAAGAGCCCCACGCAGACCCUGCUUUCUUCCCGCAGAGGCCCCACCGUCUUAUGAGCAGAGCUGCGGCGGCGUGGAACCCAGCCUGACCCCUGAGAGCUGACCCCGUGCUGCCUUCUCCAGGCAGGCCUGGCCUCUGCCCUGGGACUGGGGCGCCCAGGGCCUCGUGCCUUCUCUCUUGGCCUAGCCUGGCCCACUCAGGACCUGCCCAGCCUCUGCCAGCUCCUCUGGCAUCCGCCCUCUUCUCCCUGGGGCUGGGGUGGGGGUGGCAGGGAGCUGGGACCUGGAGAGACAACUCCUGUAAAUAAAACACUUUAUUUGUAGA